GCCUAACGGUUCUGCUCAGCUGCCUAAAGGUUCUGCUCAGGUGCCUAACGGUUCUGCUCAGCUGCCUAACGGUUUUGCGCAGCCAUUUUCUCCCGGGAGAGGUUGGAGUGUCCAAAAGCUUGGCCCGACUGAGAUUUCUAGUCUUGUCAGGGCGGAUGCAGGGACUGAAGAAGGGCGAGGGCGAGCGGCGGGGACUGGGGAAGGGCGAGCAGCGGGAGGCACGGGCUCUCUCUAGCAGGUGGCUGCAGCCAUGGAGAGGCUCUCUGCCGCCCCUGUCAAGGGCCAGACGGGCCCAGAGCGCCCGAGCCCCUUCAGUCAGCUGGUCUACACCAACAACGACUCUUACGUGAUUCACCAUGGGGAUCUCAGGAAGAUCCACAAAGCUGCCUCCCGGGGCCAAGCCUGGAAGCUGGAGAGGAUGAUGAAGAAGACGACAAUGGACCUGAACAUAAGAGAUGCGAAGAAGAGGACUGCUCUAUACUGGGCCUGUGCCAAUGGCCAUGCAGAAGUAGUAACACUUCUGGUAGAUAGAAAGUGUCAGCUUGACGUCCUUGAUGGUGAAAACAGGACCAUUCUGAUGAAGGCUCUGCAAUGCCAGAGGGAGGCUUGUGCAAAUAUUCUCAUAGAUUCUGGUGCUGAUCCAAAUAUUGUAGAUGUGUAUGGCAACACAGCUGUCCAUUAUGCUGUUAACAGUGAGAAUUUGUCAGUGGUGGCAAAAUUGCUGUCCUGUGGUGCAGACAUCGAAGUGAAGAACAAGGCUGGCCACACACCACUUUUACUGGCCAUAAGGAAAAGAAGUGAGGAAAUUGUGGAAUUUUUACUGACAAAAAAUGCAAAUGCAAAUGCAGUUGAUAAGUUUAAAUGCACAGCCCUCAUGCUUGCCAUAUGUCAUGGAUCAUCAGAGAUAGUUGGCAAGCUUCUUCAGCAAAAUGUUGACAUCUGUGCUGAAGCUACAUGUGGAAUGAUUGCAGAACGUUAUGCUGUUGCUUGUGGAUUUAAUCUCUAAGUGUUUACAUUUAAAGGCUAGGUGAGAUUUUAUAGUUUGUUUCAGGUAGUUUUUGAAUGACAGUGAGUUAGUUCACUUCAUCAGCCAGAAACUAGGCAAAAAGCUGACUAGUUAGAAGGAUUAAUGGCUCCAGGAUUCUUUAUUUUAGGGCUUUAGGGACGCUAAUGUUGUCUACUUGAUUUGAAGUAUAACCCCUAUGCAUGGGAUAAAUAUAAUGUCACAAUUUUGGUUUUUCUAAUUAGUUAUUUGGGUCUCGAAAAGUCCACUUUAAGCAGAAAACCUGAUAAUGUCCCCAGGGGGCUGUCUUCCAUACCUUUAUUCUUGAAUUUUUUAAAAGAAUCUGAACCUAAGUCCAAGGAAGACAUUCCUUUUGUACAAGUCAGAAGGAUUGGCGGUGGGGGCAGAAAUGGCCAUUCUCUUCAUUUUGUUGUUUCCAUUGAUUCUAUUGCUGCAUCGUUGCCAUUGAAACUGCUCCUGCAGUCUGGUAAUGAUUGGCCUUUGUGACCAGGAAGCCCUUACUAACACAGGUUCUUCAGUCUUCAUGGUGUAGACUUCGAAGUUACUGCAUGUUUUUAAAGUUCACGUACAUAUUCUCAGCCAUUGUUUCCAAAGUACCAGCACCCCACUCUGGCAGCUAGAACUUUUAGCUUUAGCCACACACAUAGUGAGCAAAUUGACUCUUCUCCUCACACUCAAAACCUGAUGUGAAACCCACAUCUUAGCCUGGACAUGGCCUAGACCUUCAUGGUAAGUUAUCCUUUGAGUGGCUUUUUUCUAUUUUCUCUAGCCAAUAUUAGUUGUGGUCGUUUGAAACUGUAAGUCAGGUUGAAAUAAUGUUACAGGAAGAAAUUAGAGAUCCAUUUUGUCUUUGUUACCAGAUCUAUAUCCCUGGCCCUUUAUAUCCUGUGUAGCACCAUUUUGUAGGCAGUGGACGGUCUCAUUCUGUAAAAUCCCAUGUCAUCUUUCCCAAGUUGUAGUGGGUUCCAACUUGUGGUUGUCCCCUCAAGUGAUUCUUUUUUCCUAAAAGUAAAAAUCUCCCAUGCUACUUACAUCUCUACCUCGAGUUUCUAAAAUAUUUUCAAAUGCUGCAUCACCAUGAAGCCAUUCAAUAGACUUCACUAAAUCUCAAGUAAGUUGGUUAGAUUUAACAGAGCUAAGCCUCAUCCAUCACUGAUCAGUCUUCACGUAUAAAAGUAAGGAUUUGUGCUGGCUUCAGUGGUACAUAUAGUAAAAUUAAAACAACGUUGAGAAGAUCAGCAUGGUCCCCGCACAAAGAUGACAUAGAAAUCUGUAAGGUGUUGCAUAUUUCUUGGAGUCCCCAAAAGGACAUUUUACUACUUUCUAACUAGCUCCAAGGAAAUGGUGUGAGUCAAAGCAAAAUGGGUGACACCCAGUAUUGCAAUUGUGAUUUUCAUACAAAAAAUUAUUUACGUAAGGUCAUCUAUGAAAUGAGAUGUGGUAACACAUAGGAUCUUGUGUGCAAUAUUUUGUUAGUAGGGAUCUCAGAAAUGAGAAAAUACCAACUUGCAUCUUCUUUGUGGAACUUACAAAAAAUAAAGGUAGGGUUUUGUCUUCCACAGCAGCUGGAAAUGAACAUAGUGACUAAGCAUCAUUCUAACAAAGAUUUGUUGGUUCAGAGUUUAAGGAGGUAGAUAAAGACUAGUAGUAGUCCAAGCCAGAUGCUGACAUCUAUUAGUUUUCUGCCCUUGGUGUGACUGAUGAGCUCAGUAAUAGAGUAUAAUUUGGUUAUCUGAUUUAAUGAUUUAAUAUAUUUAUAAAUAUAUUUCAUUACAAAAUAUAAAAUAGCUUAGAUGCUCUGAAUUACAAGCCACAAAGAAUAGAACAUCUAAUGUCCAAAAGUAGGAAUUAAUAACAGAAAAUUGCAAUAUUUGAAUAUUAUAACCUAUGAAGAAAAACAUUUUUUUUGUUUUUUUUUUGUAAUUUAAUUUUUGUUGAGACAUGGUCUCCCUAUGUUGCCCAGGCUGGUCUUGAACUUCUGGAUUCAAGCAAUCCUCCUGUCUCAGCAUCCAAAAGUGCUUGCCUCACAAGCAUGAGCCACUGCACCAGGCCAAUAUAUUGGGUUUUAUUGGGAAUUUUAAAUUGUUUCAGCAAUAAGGUUCAAGAACAAAUUUUUUUUGCUUCAUUUUUUAUUUUAAGCAUUUUUAAAAUGUUAUCUUGUUAAAUCUUUAUAAUAACCUAGUGAAAUAAGGCCCUAAAAUCCUCAUUUUUAGAAGACAUUGAGUCUAAGAGAAGCAACUUGUUCAAGAAAAAAUACCUGUUGGUAGCCAUGCUAGGACUUAUUCCGAGUUAAGGACAUUUUCCACAUGUCAAGCUACCUCUAGUUAAUUUACUGAGUUAUACUGCCCUCACUUCAUGAGUGUUUUAUCUUUCUUUCUUCUUUAAUUAGAAGCUUAAUAAGUUCAUAGAGCUUACAAACUUAAAGUCUAUGGAAAAAGUAAUGUUCUGAUGUUAGCUCUAAUAUUGUCUGAAAUACCCUAAGAAUGUAAUAAAUUUGGUAAAUAUUUUUUAUAUCAAUGUUAAAAUAGUGAUUUUAUUUAUUUCAUUUUUA